AUGCGACCUGGCUGCAGCCUCACUGCCCGCACCUGCCUGAGCCUAAUGGACUCUUGUUGGACAUCUGGGGCUGCUGGAGUCCAGAGUCCCCUCGCAGUGCCACUCCCCCAGCCCUCUACACCCCCACCCUGCCCAUCCAUUUCCCUGCGGCCACGGCUGCCACGCCACCUCCUGGUAUUGAGCAGUGAUAUGAGAAGGUGUGAAGGAUACGGGGGCACCAGGGACAGGCUGGCAGGCAAGAUGGAUGAGGGGGCAGGGGGCCAGCAGGCGCCUCGGGCAGGCAGGGCGGGCGGGCCAGCCGGGGAGGGGUGUGCAGGGAGGCCUGCCUGUGUCUGUGCGCGUGCUGUGUGGAAUCAAGGCCACUGCCAACCCAGCAUCCCCAAGACAGGAUUCUGGAGGAGGUAUGGGGGGCUCCAGCCAGACGACCCACUCUGUGCCAUUCAGCAAGAGUCAAAAGGCCAGCGAGCACUCUCAACCAAGGAACUGGCAGCCUCUCAGGGGGACCUCCAGCCUUGGACAGCACAGCCCGAGAGUGGCUUGGAGAAGGGCCGCUGCACGCCCCAGAGCCUGCAUCUCACCUUCGGAGACCAGGGGUCCAGCUCGAGUAGGAAGACCACGACCUCAGGACGUGGACGAAGGGCGAUCGAGGAGGCAAGGACCGUCCUGCCGAGAGACUACAGCUUGUACUUGACACUCGAUGCUUCUGGCAAGCUGUCAUCUCUGGGCCCUGAGGAAUGCUGGCUUCUAGAGGGACUGAGCAAAGGACAGGCUCCCCCCACCAGAGUCCCUGAAAGUGUUGAGGGGCAGCACAUUGGCUGCGACGGGCAGCGGAGCUGGCUGGGUGAUGCGUGGGGCCCACACUUCCGUCCUCUCUCCACAGCCUUCCUAUCUGCUGGCCUCGGCAUACUUGCACCCUCAGAGACCUACCCCCUACCUACAACCAGCUCUGGCUGGGAGCCCCGGCUGGGGUCACCAUUCCCAUCAGGCCCUUGCACCAGCUCUACUGGGGCCCAAGCUGUGGCCGAGCCCACUGGGCAGGGCCCCAAGAACCCACGUGUGUCCAGAGUGACAGUUCAGCUGGAGAUGAAGCCUCUGUGGGAGGAAUUCAACCAGCUGGGCACUGAGAUGAUCGUCACCAAGGCAGGCAGGAGGAUGUUCCCCCCCUUCCAGGUGAAGAUCCUGGGCAUGGACUCCCUGGCCGACUACGCCCUGCUCAUGGACUUCAUCCCCCUGGACGACAAGAGAUACAGGUAUGCCUUCCACAGCUCGGCCUGGCUGGUGGCGGGCAAGGCAGACCCAGCCACACCUGGCCGCGUGCACUUCCACCCCGACUCGCCAGCCAAGGGUGCCCAGUGGAUGCGCCAGAUUGUGUCCUUUGACAAGCUCAAGCUGACCAACAACCUGCUGGAUGACAAUGGCCACAUCAUUCUCAACUCUAUGCACCGCUACCAGCCCCGUUUCCACGUGGUCUUCGUGGACCCACGCAAGGACAGUGAGCGCUAUGCCCAGGAGAACUUCAAGUCCUUCAUCUUCACAGAGACCCAGUUCACAGCAGUGACAGCCUAUCAGAACCACAGGAUCACCCAGCUGAAAAUCGCCAGCAACCCUUUUGCCAAAGGCUUUAGAGAGAGUGACCUGGACUCCUGGCCUGUGGCCCCACGGCCCCUGCUCAGUGUCCCAGCCCGGAGUCACAGCAGCCUCAGUCCCUGUGUGCUGAAGGGUGCCACAGACAGGGAGAAAGACCCCAACAAAGCUUCAGCUUCCACCUCCAAGACCCCUGCUUGGCUCCAUCAUCAGCUGCUGCCCCCACCUGAGGUCCUGCUGGCCCCGGCCACCUACAGGCCUGUCACGUAUCAGAGCCUGUACUCUGGAGCCCCGAGCCACCUAGGGAUCCCAAGGACCCGACCAGCACCAUACCCCCUCCCCAACAUCCGGGCUGAUAGGGAUCAAGGAGGCCUGCCUCUCCCAGCUGGGCUGGGGCUCCUGUCCCCCACUGUGGUGUGCCUGGGGCCUGGCCAGGACUCCCAGUGAUGCCAGAAGCCCUGGGGGGAAGCCCUGCUACCCUGGACCUUACACCGGGUGUGGGAAUCAGCCUCUGCCCCGCCCCCUCCAGCCCCAUCUCUGUCUCAAGGAGAGCAGGGUAGGUGAAAGUCUAGAGAAAGAGGCUACCUGCCCAGGGUCACAGCAAGGCUGGGACCAUGGCAAGCUUGGAACCAGGACUUCUAUCUCCCAACCCCAGCAGCCUGAAUACUGUGCCCUCUUGCUUUGGGGGUAACUCCCGAAAACCCUGCCUUACCUCUCCCUUCCCCCUAACAUUAAACUAUUUGGCAUGA